AUCUGAGGGCGCACGGCCCGCGACCGAGCGUGCGGACUGGCCUCCCAAGCGUGGGGCGACAAGCUGCCGGAGCUGCAAUGGGCCGCGGCUGGGGAUUCUUGUUUGGCCUCCUGGGCGCCGUGUGGCUGCUCAGCUCGGGCCACGGAGAGGAGCAGCCCCCGGAGACAGCGGCACAGAGGUGCUUCUGCCAGGUUAGUGGUUACUUGGAUGAUUGUACCUGUGAUGUUGAAACCAUUGAUAGAUUUAAUAACUACAGGCUUUUCCCAAGACUACAAAAACUUCUUGAAAGUGACUACUUUAGGUAUUACAAGGUAAACCUGAAGAGGCCGUGUCCUUUCUGGAAUGACAUCAGCCAGUGUGGAAGAAGGGACUGUGCUGUCAAACCAUGUCAAUCUGAUGAAGUUCCUGAUGGAAUUAAAUCUGCGAGCUACAAGUAUUCUGAAGAAGCCAAUAAUCUCAUUGAAGAAUGUGAACAAGCUGAACGACUUGGAGCAGUGGAUGAAUCUCUGAGUGAGGAAACACAGAAGGCUGUUCUUCAGUGGACCAAGCAUGAUGAUUCUUCAGAUAACUUCUGUGAAGCUGAUGAUUGGAUCUGCUGGUGGUCAUCUAAGAAGAAAGUAUUUGACAUUCAGUCCCCUGAAGCUGAAUAUGUAGAUUUGCUUCUUAAUCCUGAGCGCUACACUGGUUACAAGGGACCAGAUGCUUGGAAAAUAUGGAAUGUCAUCUACGAAGAAAACUGUUUUAAGCCACAGACAAUUAAAAGACCUUUAAAUCCUUUGGCUUCUGGUCAAGGGACAAGUGAAGAGAACACUUUUUACAGUUGGCUAGAAGGUCUCUGUGUAGAAAAAAGAGCAUUCUACAGACUUAUAUCUGGCCUACAUGCAAGCAUUAAUGUGCAUUUGAGUGCAAGAUAUCUUUUACAAGAGACCUGGUUAGAAAAGAAAUGGGGACACAACAUUACAGAAUUUCAACAGCGAUUUGAUGGAAUUUUGACUGAAGGAGAAGGUCCAAGAAGGCUUAAGAACUUGUAUUUUCUCUACUUAAUAGAACUAAGGGCUUUAUCCAAAGUGUUACCAUUCUUCGAGCGCCCAGAUUUUCAACUCUUUACUGGAAAUAAAAUUCAGGAUGAGGAAAACAAAAUGUUACUUCUGGAAAUACUUCAUGAAAUCAAGUCAUUUCCUUUGCAUUUUGAUGAGAAUUCAUUUUUUGCUGGGGAUAAAAAAGAAGCACACAAACUAAAGGAGGACUUUCGACUGCAUUUUAGAAAUAUUUCAAGAAUUAUGGAUUGUGUUGGUUGUUUUAAAUGUCGUCUGUGGGGAAAGCUUCAGACUCAGGGUUUGGGCACUGCUCUGAAGAUCUUAUUUUCUGAGAAAUUGAUAGCAAAUAUGCCAGAAAGUGGACCUAGUUAUGAAUUCCAUCUAACCAGACAAGAAAUAGUAUCAUUAUUCAACGCAUUUGGAAGAAUUUCUACAAGUGUGAAAGAAUUAGAAAACUUCAGGAACUUGUUACAGAAUAUUCAUUAAAGAAAACAAGCUGAUAUGUGCCUGUUUCUGGACAAUGGAGGCGAAAGAGUGGAAUUUCAUUCAAAGGCAUAAUAGCAAUGACAGUCUUAAGCCAAACAUUUUAUAUAAAGUUGCUUUUGUAAAGGAGAAUUAUAUUGUUUUAAGUAAACACAUUUUUAAAAAUUGUGUUAAGUCUAUGUAUAAUACUACUGUGAGUAAAAGUAAUACUUUAAUAAUGUGGUACAAAUUUUAAAGUUUAAUAUUGAAUAAAAGGAGGAUUAUCAAAUUCAUAUAUGAUAAAAGUGAAUGUUCUAAGUCUCUCAAACUAGCGUUUUAUGUAAUAAUAUGUAAUAUAAAUAAAACUAUGGUAAAUGUGACAAGCAUUUAAUAGGAAAAUGCUAAGGAGGCCUCAUAAAUGACCCAUAAUUACCAACGUAGAAUUUUUCAGUACAUUUAGGGUUGCUGGAUUUAGCAAAUAAAAAUAAAGAUUGCCCAGUUAGAUUUGAAUUUCAGAUAAACAAUUAGUUUUUUAAUAUUUUACAUGGAAUAUUUGGAAAAUACUUAUACUAAAAAAUUAUUUGUUUGAAAUUCAAAUUUAACUGGGAGUCUUGUAUUUUAUCUGGCAAUCCUAAAAUACAUUGGUAUGAAACAAAUCACUUUUAGAAGUAUAUUGCUAUUUUGAUUGGGUUGUUUUUGUGUGUAGAAACGUACAAUAACAACUCAAAGGCACAGGAGAUUUCUAAACAUUGUGAAAAGUUGAAUAGAUUAUAUAUUUAUUCUCAUAAUACUUUCACUAAUACUAAAUAAAAUUUGGGGAACACUUUUUAUUUUUAUAUAAUUUCCAAUUUACAGAAAAGUUUCAAAAAUAGUACAAAGAGCUCUCUUACCCAGAUUCACUAAUUGUUCAUACGUGCUUUAUCUUUCAUGCUUUCUCUGUACACACACACACACACACAAAUUUUUCCUCAAUCAUUUGAAAGUCAGUUAUAGGCAUCAUGCCCCUUAAACCCUAAAUACUUCAGUGUGUAAUACUGAAUAAUUACUAAAAAUGAUUUUCUCAGAAAAAAAAACUCCCACAAUUCUGGAACUAUAAUACUGUAAGCCUUAGAAUAAAUAAUACUUUCAAGUUCCAAUCUAAAGUUCUUUUUGAGUUUUGUUGCCCGUUUUAUGCUUGAUGUGUAUAGUAAUAGGGUAGGCUAUUUAUUUUAUUAAAAUUUUUUUUAGAGACAAGGUUUUGCUGUGUUGCCCAAGCUGGAACUUGAACGACUGGGCUGAAGUGAUCUUCCCACCUCAGCCUCCCAAGUAGCUGGGAAUACAGGUGUCUGCCACCAUACCCAGUUUCAUUUUUGUUUUUUAUACCCGAAGUUCAUUUCCUUUGUCUCCCUAAAACUGAACUGUAAUUUUGGGAGGUUUUCAUUAGUGGAAGCUCUUCAUUUAUAAAGCUAUUUGAAGGGGUUUAGGAAUUUAUAUCACAUGGUAAUUGUAGAGAAAAAGAAGCUAUAUACCUCAAAAUCGUGCCCUCUUUACAUAUGUCUUAUCAGGUAUAACAUGUUGAAAUGUCACAUUAGUAGUAAAGUGGGGUUUAUUUAUAUAGUGGUUAAGAAAUGUCAGUUUACACUGCUGUAUACUUCUUCUUCUGUGUCCCUAAGGCCUGGUACAGUGCCAAGCACAUACUUGGUAUCCAAUAAAUAUUUGUUGGAUGAAUGUAUGCAUAUGUAUUCAGUAUAUUUUAAAUGAAUAAUCACAGAAGUAAGUUUAAUAAUUUGUCCUAUUUUUCUCUGUCACUUCCUUUUUCUCUAAGGCAGGAAAGGAAAGACAUUAAACCAUUAAUUAAGUCAAUCCUCUUGGAGACUCAAAAGACUAUGAAGUGAUCACUCUAUAUAAAAUAUAAAUACAGUGUGGGUUCAAAUGGCCAUUUUUUGUGUGUCCCUCUCUCUCAUCUUAUGCUUCCCUUCCUUUUUUUAUUUUUAUUUUUUGGAGACGGAGUCUUGCUGUGUCGCCCAGGUUGGAGUGCAGUGGCGUGAUCUUAGCUCACUGCAAGCUCUGCCUUCCAGGUUCACGCCAUUCUUCUGCCUCAGCCCCCUGAGUAGCUGGGACUACAGGCGCCCGCCACCACGCCCGGCUAAUUUUUUUUUUUUUUUUUUUGUAUUUUUAGUAGAGGCAGUGUUUCACCGUGUUAGCCAGGAUGGUCUUGAUCUCCUGACCUCGUGAUCCACCCACCUCGACCUCCCAAAGUGCUGGGAUUACAGGCGUGAGCCACCACGCCCGGCCUCUUUUUUUUUUAGCUGCCAAUCUUUUUGAAGGAAUAUUCUUACCUCUACUUUGUCACCUUCUACUGGCUCCUUAACUAAAAUCUGCCAUUUGGCUCUCUGGUUAACAGUCCCUUCCUGUAAAGUCUAAAAUCUUAAUUCUAAAUCCACAGUUUAAUUCACAAGCUAGUACUUGACUUUUUUUCUGUAUUUGACAUUUUUGACAACCCCUACUUUAAAGAUUUAUUCCCUUGACUUCUUACAUUUUGCUCACUCCUGAACCACCCCCCACCUUUUGGCCUCUUCAUUUAUUCCUUAAAUGUUAUUCCUCAGACCUCCAUUUUUUUUUUCUCUCUUAAUCACAACACCACUUCUCACGCUUGGGUAAUUUUAAUUCAGCAGUUCCUAAAUCCUUAUCUUUAGCCAGACUCCUCAAUCCAUCUGCCUGUUGCACUUUUCUUGGUUGUCCCAGAGACACCUGUGUGUGUCUUAAAACAUUCAUUCUCUGCAAAACCUACUCUAAUGCCUGUGUCCCUUACUUUGGUUAAUUUUAGAACCAUUAUAUUCUAAGUUUUCUAGGCUCAUUCCUCUCCUCCACCUUCCCCUAUCAUUUAGUGUCUAAGUUUUACUGAUUUUAUCUCCACCUCUCUGAUACAUCACUCUUUCAUCUUCAUUGCUAUUAUUAAUAAAUACCUACAGUACUAACCUGCCUCCUAUACCUAGCUGGUCUCCUCUCUGUUGCUCAAUGUUACCACAGCAGGCUUUCUAGAAGCACUCUGACAGUGUUACUCCCUAAUAUCCUUCAGUGACUUCAGGAACUUUCAGGAGAAAGCCAAACUCCUCUGUUUGGUGUACAAGGUCUUCUGAUGUGUUUCCUCCACCGAAUGUUCUGGUGAAACAGACUUACACUUCUUCAGAAGCCACAUUUGGCCAGGCCUCCCGCCUUGGUAAAUGCUGUACUCUUUGCAUCAAGUAUGCUAGUCAUCCUUCCCCACUUGGAAAAUUCCUAUGCAUCUUGCAGGCCUGACAUAAGCAUUUCCUCUGUGAAACCUCCUUUGCUCCACUCAAGGAGAGUCAUCUAACUUCCACUUUCGUGUCACCACUGUAAUUACAACCUACCUCUAUUGUAUGUCACUUAAAUCGUACUGUAUUGUUUUAUUUUUCAAAAGUCUUUACUAGAAUGUGAGCUCCUUAAGGGCAGGAAAAGGAACCUUUUUAUUUUUUGCAUCUCCAUAGCAUAGUUUUUGGCAUAUGAAUGUUUAAUAAAUGUUUGUUGAAUAAAUUGAUUUUAAAGUGACAUCUUUAUUAUAUUAGAGGUCCUACCUAUAUUCCAAAUACUUUCACUCCCUUCACUUUACAGCAAGGGUCAGUAGAGUCCCAAGGAUUUGUAGACUUUAGGGGGUCAAUAAAGCUGAAAUUGUAUUCAA